CUCCUGGCCUUAAGCAAUCCUCCUGCAUUAGCUUCUCAAAUUGCUGGAAUUUCAGGCAUGAGCCACCAUGCCUGGCCUGGGCUAGUCCUAUAUUCUCUAGAGUUCUCUUUACUUUGUGCUAGCCAGUCUCUCAUUAUGCUAUUCACCUGUUAUAAUGAAUAAUUCUCUGUAUUAAAUUUUACCACUUUAAACUUUUGAGCGGUUUAUGCUUCCUGAUUGGACUCUGACUAAUAUGUUAGGAAGGGUCCCAGGAGAUAAACCCACACAGAUGGGAUUUGGGCAUAGGUUUGGUUUCCCAGGGGGCAGUGCUGAGCUCUUUGCCAGUGGGAAAUGGGAUGCUGGUGAUUUCCAGGAAGUGACCUCACAAUGACUCAAGCUACCACUUACUGUUGAUUGUGACGAAAUGCCAGCUGAGGCACAUGCCUUGGGAGCUAAGUGGUUGCUGCACUUGACCACUGUGAAGACUGGUGUGGGAAGGGUCGUUUUGGAUGCACUUGAGCAGGGAUCCCCAAACCCUGAGCCAUGGAGCCGUAAGGAGCCACACAGCAGGAGGUGGGACCAUCCAGUUGCAGGAAAACAAGCUUAACACGCCCACUGAUUCUACAUUAUGCCUCUCCAGGCCCAGAACUUUCUCCAGUCAGCCUCCACAGACCAAGCUCAUGACUCACAAUGGCCUAUUUAGGCCCAUACCCUACCUCACGGCAGUCUCCGCAGAUGAGGCUACUGCCUCACAACAGCCUCCACAGGCACAGCUCCACCGUUACAAUGGCCUCUUUAGACCCAGCUCCUGCCUCCCAGCCUUCUCUCCAGGCCCUGAACUUCCUCAAGUCGACCUCACCAGGCCCAGCUCAUGCUUCUUGGCAGCCUCUCCAGGCCCAGCUCCUGCAUCUUGGCAGCCUCUCCAGGCCCAGCCUCUGCCUCCUGUCAGCCUCUACAGUCCCAACAUCUGUCUCACAGCAGAUUCUUCAGGCCCAGCAUCUGCCUCACUGUGGACCACCCAAGCCAAGCUCCCAACCUUUCAGCAGCUUCUACACACCCAGCUCCUGCCACCCAGUGGCCUCUUUAGGCCAAGCUCAUGCCUCACAAGGGCCUUUCCAGGCCCAACUUUUGUCUCAUGGCAACCUUCCCUGGCCAGAUUCCUGCCUGUCUCCCAGCAGCCUAGACAGGCCCAGGUCUUGCCUCACACUGGCCUGUCUACAUCCAGCUCUUGCCUCACGGUGGCCUCUCCAGGCCCAGCUCCUGUCCCAGGACGUCAUCUCCAGGCCCAAAACUUCCUCAAGUCAGCCUCUCUAGUCCCAACUGCUGCCUCCUGGUGGCCUAUGAAGGCCCAAAAUCUCCUCAAGUUGACCUCUCCAGGCCCAGCUCCUGCCUCCUGUCAGCAUCUACAGGCCCAACCUCUGCCUCAUGGGGGCUUCUCCAGGCCCAGCUCUUCCUCUGGGCUGAGUCUACAGGCACAACUGCUGCCUCACAACAGCCUUUUUUGGCCCAGUUCCUGUCCAGCUCACAGCGGCCAAUGUAGGCCCAAAACUUCCUCAAGUCAAACUCUCCAGGCCCGCCUUCCGCUUCGCGGUGGCAUGAACAGGCCCAGCUUUGACUUGAGAACAGCCUCUGCAGGCCGUGCUCUUGCCUCCCAGGGGCUUCUCCAGGCCCAGCUCUUGCCUCAUGGCGGCUGCCCCAGGCCAAGUUUCUGCCUGCCUGCCAGCAGCCUCAACAGGCACAGCUCCUCCCUCACAGUGGCCCAUUUAGGCCCAACUCAUGACUGUCGGGCCAUUUCCAGGCCUAGUGCCUGCCUCCUGGCUGACUCUUGAAGCCCAAAACUUCCUCAAAUCAGCCUUUUGCCCAACUUCUGUCUACUGUCGGACUCUACAGGCCAGCCUCUGCCUCACAGUGGACCCUCCAGACCCAGAUGGUGUCUCACUGUGGCAUCCUCAGGCGAAGCUCCUGCCUUUCGGCAGCCUCUACGGGCCCAGCUCCUGCCUUGCAAUGGCCUCUUUAGGCCAAGCUCAUGCCCCACGGCGACUUUUCCAGGCACAGCUUUUGCCUUUUGCAGCCUGUCCAGGCCCAGAAUGUCCUUAACUCGGCAUCUCCGGGACGAGCUCAUCCUCCCAGUGCGUCUACAGGCCCGUCUCCUGCCUCACAACAACCUCCUUUGGCCCAACUCCUGCUGAGCUGCUUGGCAGUCUCUGUAGGCCACAGAGUUCUU